GGGAUUACAGGCAUGGGCCACCACGCCUGGCCAGCAGGAGGAUUUUUUAACAAAUUGUUGAGUCAUGGCUAUCUUAAUGCAAGACUUCACUUUUAGCUUAUUUAAAAAGUCUGUCAUUGUAGCGAUAGCCUUAGGGAAGAUGCCUCAUCCCUGCCUAACAGAUUUUAGGUUAGAAAAUGGAAUUUCUCUUGUUUUUGUGAAUCGUUGCUUAACCUAAAUAAUAAUAGUCUCAAAUAUAAAACAAACCCUGAUAAAAGUCAAGCAUCUCGUUCUAAAAGAUAUUGGGUAUUAUAGAGUGUUAAGUGCUUUUUUAAGAUGAAGUUGUUAUGUGAGUGACAGAUUUAUACAGGAGCAAGUCCCUACUGAAGUUGUUCAGCCAGCUGCAACUUGACAAACCCCAGGCAGCCUUUUUUCUUUUUCUUCGUAUUUCGGUUCACGUCUGAAAGGCUUUCACGGUCCAUCCAUUUUAGAGCAUUCGGCUGGUUGCCCCAUGUGCCCUUCCCUGUGGACUUGAGUGUGUCUGUGGGUAAGGGCGGCAGUGCACGUGUUCAUCCAUGGCCGGAGGCCGCGGAUGGUGUUGCAGCCGCCAAGAGGGUGAAGCUGCUGCCCAUCAAGCGACCCCAGCUCCCAGUUAGAAGCUGCAGCAAGGUUCACAGGCGUCCACGUGUGCGUCUUAGAAUCGAAGGAGCGUGGAGGAUUCGGAAGGCUAGUGAGUGAGCACCAGAUUGUGGAAGGUGCAGGGCCUGAGAUUCAGGAGUCAGGUCCAUAGAGGCCCGUUGGGAAGCUCUGGCUGUGCAGAAGACGAGGUGGGAAGCAUAGUCAGCACCUUGAGUUUCAAGCUUUUCUUACUUUUCUGUGCAGAUUAAGUCUUACAGGAAAGCCCAGCCAAUAAAACUAAGGCCCACAGAACGUAUGGGUGUGGCUGUGCGGCCCACUGCCCUCCAGGCUCAGCUCUAGCCGCCAGGAAUCAGGUGAAAUCAGAAAUCAGCACGUCCAAAAAGAGAAGGUGCUCGCUUCCUCCUCUUCCUGUGUGUUACUUCCCUGCUCUCCUGCCCGUGUCCCCAUGAGGCUUCCUUUAGAAUUCUCUCCUAGCAGAGCGGCACUCCAUGAGAUCUGGGAGUGUUGGAGAAGGCUGAGGGGUUGCUUGGGUUUGGGGUGACUGGGAUGGGAGUUGGAACCCGUUCAUGGCAGAGAGACAAGCCUGCAGCCUAGGGACCAUUCUUGUUCUGGCUCUUAGGAGAAAGGCCAGGGCAGUGCAGGCAGCACUUUGACUUGGACAUUUUAUUUUUUUGCUUCUAUUCCGCUGUUUUUUCUUGGUAGAUGAAUGUCUUGGGCAUAGGACUAAUUUAGUUAUACAGAUUUUUCUUUUUAAAUAAUUUGGUUCCACUUUUCUCCCUUGAAAUAGAACUGUCUGUUGAGGGGCUGUGCUUUUUUGUAGAGUGGUAGGAGAGGGUCAAAGGAGAACAGUUUCAACAUCUGCCCCGUGCAGCACACGCGGGGCAGUCAGCAGCAAGGCGCUCAGCUCCUGCCCGUGGAGGCUUCGGUUGAAGGAAUGCAGGAAUGCCCUGCCUGUCAGACUCAGUGCGGCGGACAGGGGCAGGCGAGGCACUCAGCUCCUGCCCGUGGAGGCUUCGGUGGAAGGAAUGCCCUGCACGUCAGACUCAGUGCAGCGACGCGGGGCAGGCGAGGCGCUCAGCUUCUGCCCGUGGAGGCUUCGGUGGAAGGAAUGCCCUGCACAUUGGACUCUGCAGCAGUGCGGGUAAUAAAAGCCGCCCUCAUUCUAGGGGAGAAUAUAAUGUUUACAGCACCUUUCAAAGUCAUGAACCGGAGUUUGACUAUUUGAAAAGUCUAGAAAUUGAGGAAAAAAUUAAUAAAAUUAGGUGGUUACCACAACAGAAUGCUGCUCAUUUUCUACUGUCUACAAAUGAUAAAACUAUAAAAUUAUGGAAAAUAAGUGAACGGGAUAAAAGAGCAGAAGGUUAUAACCUGAAAGACGAAGAUGGAAGACUUCGAGACCCAUUUAGGAUCACGGCGCUACGGGUCCCAAUAUUGAAGCCCAUGGAUCUUAUGGUAGAAGCGAGUCCACGGCGAAUUUUUGCAAAUGCUCACACAUAUCAUAUAAAUUCCAUUUCAGUAAAUAGUGAUCAUGAAACAUAUCUUUCUGCAGAUGACCUGAGAAUUAAUUUAUGGCACUUAGAAAUCACAGAUAGAAGCUUUAACAUCGUGGACAUCAAGCCUGCUAACAUGGAGGAGCUGACCGAAGUCAUCACUGCAGCCGAGUUCCACCCGCACCAGUGCAACGUGUUCGUCUACAGCAGUAGCAAAGGGACCAUCCGCCUGUGUGACAUGCGCUCCUCGGCCCUGUGCGACAGACACUCCAAGUUUUUUGAAGAGCCUGAAGAUCCCAGCAGUAGGUCCUUCUUCUCAGAAAUAAUUUCAUCCAUAUCCGAUGUAAAAUUCAGUCAUAGUGGGCGGUACAUGAUGACCAGAGACUACCUGUCGGUGAAGGUGUGGGACCUCAACAUGGAGAGCAGGCCGGUGGAGACCCACCAGGUCCACGAGUACCUGCGCAGCAAGCUCUGCUCUCUCUAUGAGAACGACUGCAUCUUUGACAAGUUUGAGUGUUGCUGGAACGGUUCGGAUAGCGCCAUCAUGACCGGGUCCUAUAACAACUUCUUCAGGAUGUUUGAUAGAGACACGCGGAGGGAUGUGACCCUGGAGGCCUCGAGAGAGAGCAGCAAACCGCGCGCCAGCCUCAAACCCCGGAAGGUGUGUACGGGGGGUAAGCGGAGGAAAGACGAGAUCAGUGUGGACAGUCUGGACUUCAACAAGAAGAUCCUGCACACAGCCUGGCACCCCGUGGACAAUGUCAUUGCCGUGGCUGCCACCAAUAACUUGUACAUAUUCCAGGACAAAAUCAACUAGAGACGCGAACGUGAGGACCAAGUCUUGUCUUGCAUAGUUAAGCCGGACAUUUUUCUGUCAGAGAAAAGGCAUCAUUGUCCGCUCCAUUAAGAACAGUGACGCACCUGCUACUUCCCUUCACAGACACAGGAGAAAGCCGCCUCCGCUGGAGGCCCGGUGUGGUUCCGCCUCGGCGAGGCGCGAGACAGGCGCUGCUGCUCACGUGGAGACGCUCUCGAAGCAGAGUUGACGGACACUGCUCCCAAAAGGUCAUUACUCAGAAUAAAUGUAUUUAUUUCAGUCCGAGCCUUCCUUUCCAAUUUAUAGACCAAAAAAUUAACAUCCAAGAGAAAAGUUAUUGUCAGAUACCGCUCUUUCUCCAACUUUCCCUCUUUCUCUGCCAUCACACUUGGGCCUUCACUGCAGCGUGGUGUGGCCACCGUCCGUGUCCUCUCGGCCUUCCUCCGAGUCCAGGUGGACUCUGUGGAUGUGUGGAUGUGGCCCGAGCAGGCUCAGGCGGCCCCACUCACCCACAGCAUCCGCCGCCACCCCUUCGGGUGUGAGCGCUCAAUAAAAACAACACACUAUAAAGUGUUUUUAAAUCCAAACAGAAGUAUUGUCUUUUUAUUUAAUUUUAUUGCAUAGAAUGAAGUUAUGCAGGGUUCUUCUUUGGAACUAACUGUUUGAGAAAUGUGUGUCCUUCUUUGGCAGCGUGGGGGUAUGUGUGCAGCAUUUCUGUCCCCAAGCUGCUGCCCGCUGUGUUUCUGUAGAAGUAGCCCAUCAGAUACACCAGGUAAGGUCUGGGAAAAGCCAGAACCGAGGCCACCUCUGAGAAAGAAAAUUGCAAGGAAGAACCAAAAUUGCUGCCAUCCAGUAAGCCUGGUUUAAAGUAGCUUCAAAUUCACUACAGUUGAAGAAAUACGUGCUUGCUUUCUAAGGCUUUUGAAAAAGCACUUUGGGGAAAGUAUACUUUUUAAACAUUGCUAAAAUUACAUGCAUGCUAAAUUUCAUCCUGCAUUUCAAGCCAGCAAAAUUAAGCAAUUUUAAUUACACGAUGCCACCAGUACGUUGGUUUAUUUUCAAAGUAGGAUCUUUGAUACCAGAAAUCAAGAUUUUCCAAGACAAAUAAUACAGAGCUGUACCAAUGCUGAGUGACCAGAGCUUGCUUCCGUGGGAUUUAACACACGCCCACUACGUGUCCCCGAGGGGAGUGGGGAGUCGGGCUCCCGUGCCCCUGUGGAGAUGGAGGUGUGUGCUGAUCCCCCGUCCGCCUGUGGAGAUGAAGGUGUGUGUUGAUUCCUCCUGCUGCUGUGGAGAUGGAGGUGUGUGCUGAUCGCCCGUCACCCUGUCUAGAUGAAGGUAUGUGCUGAUUGCCUGUGCCCCUGUGGAGAAGGAGGUGUGUGCUGAUCCCCUGUGCCCUGUGGAGAUGGAGGUGUGUGCUGCUCCCUCGUGCCCCUGUGGAGAUGGAGGUGUGUGCUGAUCCCCCAUCCCAUCCCCCUGUCUAGAUGAAGGUGUGUGCUGAUUCCUCAUGCCCCUGUCUGGAUGAAGGUGUGUGCUGAUCCCCCGUCCCCCUGUGGAGAUGAAGGUGUGUGCUGAUCCCCCGUGCCCCUGUGGAGAUGAAGGUGCGUGCUGAUCCCCCAUCUCCCUGUGGAGAUGAAGGUGUGUGCUGAUCCCCAUCCCCCUGUGGAGAUGAAGGGAUAUGCUGAUCCCCUGUCCCACUGUGGAGAUGAAGGGGUGUGCUGAUCCCCCGUCCCCCUGUGGAGAUGAAGGUGUGUGCUGAUCCCCCAUCUCCCUGUGGAGAUGAAGGGGUGUGCCAAUCCCCCGCGCCCCUGUGGAGAUGGAGGCGUGUGCUGAUCCCCAUCCCCCUGUGGAGAUGAAGGUGUGUGCUGAUCCCCCAUCCCCAUGUGGAGAUGAAGGGGUGUGUUGAUCCCCUGUCCCCCUGUGGAGAUGGUGUGUGCUGAUCCCCGUCCCCCUGUGGAGAUGAAGGUGUGUGCUGAUCCCCCAUCUCCCUGUGAAGAUGAAGGGGUGUGCUGAUCCCCCGUGCCCCUGUGGACAUGGAGGCGUGUGCUGAUCCCCCGUCCCCCUGUGGAGAUGAAGGUGUGUGCUGAUCCCCCAUCCCCAUGUGGAGAUGAAGGGGUGUGUUGAUCCCCCGUCCCCCUGUGGAGAUGAAGGUGUGUGCUGAUCCCCGUCCCCCUGUGGAGAUGAAGGGGUGUGCUGAUCCCCCAUGCCCUGUGGAGAUGGAGGUGUGUGCUGAUCCCUCGUGCCCCUGUGGAGAUAGAGGUGUGUACUGAUCCCCUGUUCCCCUAUCUAGAUGAAGGUGUGUACUGCUGAUCCCCCGUCCCCCUGUGGAGAUGAAGGUGUGUGCUGAUCCCCCAUCCCCCUGUGGAGAUGAAGGGGUGUGCUGAUCCCCCGUCUUCCUGUGGAGAUGAAGGUGUGUGCUGAUUCCUCAUGCCCCUGUGGAGAUGGAGGUGUGUGCUGAUCCCCCAUCCCCCUGUGGGGAUGAAGGUGUGUGCUGAUCCCCCAUCCCCCUGUGGAGAUGAAGGGGUAUGCUGAUCCCCCGUCCCCCUGUGGAGAUGAAGGUGUGUGCUGAUCCCCCAUCCCCCUGUGGAGAUGAAGGGGUAUGCUGAUCCCCUGUCCCCCUGUGGGGAUGAAGGUGUGUGCUGAUCUCUUGUCCCCCUGUGGAGAUGGAGGUGUGUGCUGAUCCCCCAUCCCCCUGUGGAGAUGAAGAUGUGUGCUGAUCCCCCGUCCUCCUGUGGAGAUGAAGGUGUGUGCUGCUUCCUCGUGCCCCUGUGGAGAUGGAGGUGUGUGCUGGUCCCCCGUCCCCCUGUGGAGAUGGAGGUGUGUGCUGAUCCCCCGUCCCCCUGUGGAGAUGGAGGCGUGUGCUGAUCCCCCAUCCCCCUGUGGAGAUGAAGGCGUGUGCUGAUCCGCCAUCCCACUGUGGAGAUGAAGGCGUGUGCUGAUCCCCCAUCCCCCUGUGGAGAUAAAGGUGUGUGCUGAUCCCCCAUCCCCCUGUGGAGAUGAAGGCGUGUGCUGAUCCGCCAUCCCACUGUGGAGAUGAAGGCGUGUGCUGAUCCCCCAUCCCCCUGUGGAGAUGAAGGCGUGUGCUCAUCCCCCAUCCCCCUGUGGAGAUGAAGGCGUGUGCUGAUCCGCCAUCCCACUGUGGAGAUGAAGGUGUGUGCUGAUCCCCCAUCCCCCUGUGGAGAUGAAGGUGUGUGCUGAUCCCCGGUCCCCCUGUGGAGAUGAAGGUGUGUGCUGAUCCCCCGUCCUCCUGUGGAGAUGAAGGCGUGUGCUGAUCCCCCGUCCCCCUGUGGAGAUGAAGGCGUGUGCUGAUCCGCCGUCCCCCUGUGGAGAUGAAGGCGUGUGCUGAUCCGCCAUCCCCCUGUGGAGAUGAAGGCGUGUGCUCAUCCCCCAUCCCCCUGUGGAGAUGAAGGCGUGUGCUGAUCCGCCAUCCCACUGUGGAGAUGAAGGUGUGUGCUGAUCCCCCAUCCCCCUGUGGAGAUGAAGGCGUGUGCUGAUCCCCGGUCCCCCUGUGGAGAUGAAGGUGUGUGUUGAUCCCCCAUCCCCCUGUGGAGGUGAAGGUGUGUGCUGAUUACUAAUCCACAUGGGCAAGAACAGGAUGUCCGUCAUUACCCUGAAUCAAUGCUAACACAGUGCCACUUGAGUUCACAUUAAGUUAGAAAUUGAGAAUCUAAAGGUACCUUUAUUUUAACUAAAAAAUAAUUUAUAUACUGUAUAUUGAUUGUGACACAAUUUACAAAGUCUGAGGUGUGGAACAGUUAUUUAAGCAUUAGUCAACCCUGGUCCUUAAGACAGUUCUAGUAAAAUGGGAUUGUAUAUAUUUGUUCAACUAUUUUGACCAAAAAGUUCAAUAAAUUUUAAAUGUUUAACUGGA